AGUCUGUUGCCUUCCAGGGGCCAAGAGCUGCUCUGAUCACCCAGGGAUUCUCUCUCCAACCCAAGUGCCUCCAGCUGACCUCUGGCUCCUGUCCUCUGGCUCCACCUGCACCGCCCUGCUCUUCCUAAGGGGCCAGGAAGCCCCCAGAAGCUCUACCAUCGACGUGGGUGGUGGCACCCGGCUCACCCUGAGAGCAGAGGCCGUGCAGGGGGCUCAGUUCUGAGCCCCAGCCGGCCCACCAUGGCACGGCGGUUCCAGGAGGAGCUGGCCGCCUUCCUCUUCGAGUAUGACACCCCCCGCAUGGUGCUGGUGCGUAAUAAGAAGGUGGGCGUUAUCUUCCGACUGAUCCAGCUGGUGGUCCUGGUCUACGUCAUCGGGUGAGUCCGGGCGCCUCCCGCUGCCUGCACCAGCCCCUACCCCGGGCCUGUCCUCCAGACUCUGACAUCCCUUGCGUGACACCAGCGAGCCCCUCUUCCUCUCCAUCCAGGGGAAGGCCUUCCUGGCAAGCCACUGUGCGAGAAUAGAAAAUCCUGCCAACUCGCUGUUGAGAUGGGGACGAGGCCGGAGGGGAAGCCCUGCCCGGGGGCCUUCGGUGAACAGGAGGCAGAGUCUCUGGGUUCUGAGGAGCCGGCUCAGUGUUAUGGUUCCUUUGAGUGGUUAGUGGUGUUCAGGGCCAGGGCACCACCAACCACAGCCACUGAGUCCUCGACCUCUGACCGCCUGCCAAACCAGGCCGCCACUGACACACAGAGGCCAUACCCCACACCCGUCACCCCAUAUGACAAGUUAGAGAGAGACAGACUCUGCUGCCAGCUUCCCUGCCUGAGCAAGGGACAUCCAGGGACGUUUGAGGCCCCCGGAGCAGAGAAACUCUCACAUUCUGAAUACCUGGUGCCUUCAUGUUGGCAUGUCAGGCGGAGGACAGAGAUUGGUUCUGGUCCCAGGGAUGAUAGUUCCUUUCUGGGCAUCUCCGGACCUGUCCCACCGGGCUGGGAGUGCAGAAUCAGAGGCAGCGUGGGACGCUCCUGCAGUAUGGUUGUCUCGGGAGCCAAGACAGGCCUGGCAGAGGCUGGCACACUUGUGGGUGUUUCUCUAUGAGAAGGGCUACCAGACCUCGAGCGGCCUCAUCAGCAGUGUCUCUGUGAAACUCAAGGGCCUGGCCGUGACCCAGCUCCCUGGCCUCGGCCCCCAGGUCUGGGAUGUGGCUGACUACGUCUUCCCAGCCCAGGGGGACAACUCCUUCGUGGUCAUGACCAAUUUCAUCGUGACCCCGAAGCAGACUCAAGGCUACUGCGCAGAGCACCCAGAAGGGGGCAUAUGCAAGGAAGACAGUGGCUGUACCCCUGGGAAGGCCAAGAGGAAGGCCCAAGGCAUCCGCACGGGCAAGUGUGUGGCCUUCAACGACACUGUGAAGACGUGUGAGAUCUUUGGCUGGUGCCCCGUGGAGGUGGAUGACGACAUCCCGCGCCCUGCCCUUCUCCGAGAGGCCGAGAACUUCACUCUUUUCAUCAAGAACAGCAUCAGCUUUCCACGCUUCAAGGUCAACAGGCGCAACCUGGUGGAGGAGGUGAAUGCUGCCCACAUGAAGACCUGCCUCUUUCACAAGACCCUGCACCCCCUGUGCCCAGUCUUCCAGCUUGGCUACGUGGUGCAAGAGUCAGGCCAGAACUUCAGCACCCUGGCUGAGAAGGGUGGAGUGGUUGGCAUCACCAUCGACUGGCACUGUGACCUGGACUGGCACGUACGGCACUGCAGACCCAUCUAUGAGUUCCAUGGGCUGUACGAAGAGAAAAAUCUCUCCCCAGGCUUCAACUUCAGAACUCCAGACCCAAGACAGUCCCCUCCAUCACCCUCCUGCCACCUCAUCCCUUCCCCAAGGUUUGCCAGGCACUUUGUGGAGAACGGGACCAACUACCGUCACCUCUUCAAGGUGUUUGGGAUUCGCUUUGACAUCCUGGUGGACGGCAAGGCCGGGAAGUUUGACAUCAUCCCUACAAUGACCACCAUCGGCUCUGGAAUUGGCAUCUUUGGGGUGGCCACAGUUCUCUGUGACCUGCUGCUGCUUCACAUCCUGCCUAAGAGGCACUACUACAAGCAGAAGAAGUUCAAAUACGCUGAGGACAUGGGGCCAGGGGCGGCUGAGCGUGACCUCGCAGCUACCAGCUCCACCCUGGGCCUGCAGGAGAACAUGAGGACAUCCUGAUGCUCGGGCCCCAACUCCUGACUGGGUGCAGCGUGAGGCUUCAGCCUGGAGCCCUGGUGGGUCCCAGCCAGGGCAGAGGGGCCUCCCCAGGAAGUCUCCUACCCUCUCAGCCAGGCAGAGAGCAGUUUGCCAGAAGCUCAGGGUGCAUAGUAGGAGAGACCUGUGCAAAUCUGAGCUCCGGCUCCGACCCCACACACCCUGAGGGAGCCCUACCCUAGCCUCAGCCGCUCCUGGUGGGGAAUGGCUGGGGCUGGGCAGGACCCUCCCACACACCUGCACCCUAGCUUCGUGCUUCUCUCUCCGGACUCUCAUUAUCCAACCCGCUGCCUCCAUUUCUCUAGAUCUGUGCUCUCCGAUGUGGCAGUCAGUAACCAUAGGUGACUAAAUUAAACUAAAAUAAAAUAGAAUGAAACACAAAAUUCAAUUCCUCGGCUGAACUAGCCACAUUUCAACUGCUCAGUAGAUACGUGUGGUUAGUGGCUGCCAUACUGGACAGCUCGGGGCAUUUUCACUGUCAAAGAAAGUUCUAUUAGACAGCCCUGCUUGAGCCCUGUUUCUUCCUGGCCUUCGGUUUCCCUGGGGAACUUAUCGACAAUGCAAGCUCCUGGGCCCACCCCCAGACCUCCUGAACCAAAAGCUCCAGGGCUGGCCGUAUGAUCUGUGUGGAUGGCAAACUCCCCAGGCCAUUCUGGGACCUAAGUUUAAGAAGUGCCGUCCUCGAACUUUCUGACUCUAAGCUCCUGAGCGGGAGUCAGACUUAGCCCUGAGCCUGCACUUCCUGUUCAGGUGCAGACACUGAACAGGGUCUCAAACACCUUCAGCAUGUGUGUUGUGUGCUCACGUGCCACACAGUGUCUCAUGCACACAACCCAGUGUACACACCACCUACGUGCACACAGCAUCCUUCCACACUGUGUAUGUGAACAGCUUGGGCCCUGCAAACACAACCAUCUACACACAUCUACACCCCCAAGCACACACACAUGGUCCGUGCCAUGUCACCUCCAUAGGGAAAGGCUUCUCUCCAAGUGUGCCAGGCCAGGACAGCCCUCCCAGCCAUGAAUCCUUACUCAGCUACCUCGGGUUGGGGUGGGAGCCCCAGCCAAAUCCUGGGCUCCCUGCCUGUGGCUCAGCCCCAGCUCCCAAGGCCUGCCUGGCUCUGUCUGAACAGAAGGUCUGGGGGAAGCGACGGGUGGAGUACAAUAAAGGGAAUGAGGACAAA